AGGCGCCACGUGGGAUUCGGCCCGGGUGCUCUUGUGAGCUGCUGCUCCUGCGGUUGGUGAGAUUACCUGGGUCUAGAGUGCGGAGCUGCUCCGUGGCCACGAGGACGUCACCAUGCCCAAAGCACCAAAGGGAAAAAGUGCAGGACGGGAAAAAAAAGUCAUCCAUCCAUAUAGUAGAAAAGCAGCUCAAAUUACGAGAGAGGCCCACAAACAAGAAAAAAAGGAAAAAUUGAAGAAUGAAAAGGCCUUGCGUCUCAACCUUGUUGGUGAAAAACUGCAAUGGUUUCAAAAUCAUCUUGAUCCCCAAAAAAAGAGAUAUUCAAAGAAAGAUGCUUGUGAACUAAUUGAAAGGUACUUAAAUCGAUUCAGCAGUGAGCUGGAGCAGAUUGAGUUACAUAACAGUAUCAGGGACAGGCAGGGGAGGCGGCACUGUUCCCGGGAGACCGUCAUCAAGCAGACGAUGGAGCGGGAGCGACAGCAGUUUGAGGGAUAUGGCCUUGAGAUUCCAGACAUUCUAAAUGCAAGUAAUCUGAAAACAUUUAGGGAAUGGGACUUUGAUCUGAAGAAAUUACCAAACAUUAAAAUGAGAAAAAUUUGCGCUAAUGAUGCAAUUCCCAAGACGUGCAAGAGGAAAACUAUUAUAACUGUAGACCAAGAUUUGGGGGAAUUGGAACUAAACGAUGAAUCAAGUGAUUCAGAUGAGGAAAUGACUGCAGUGGCCUAAUUGUCUUCACUUGAAUUGAAAAUAAAUAAUUUGAGAGCUUCAAAUUAUAUUCAUUGAUUAUGGUACCUAAUUGUCAUGAUACAAAAAUUUGAUACUGACAUUCUCUUAUAUGAUGAGAGUUUCAUUUGCGUUUCAAAAAUGGUGUUAUGAUACUUAUUUUAAAAUGAAGAUUGCUUUUCAUUUCCAUUAAGUUGCUAAAAUAGAUAGAUGUGAUCUGCAGAAGUUGUUUAGUCUUCAUCUGAAUUUCAGGCUGGGAGGGAGCAAUAUAACUAAGGACAAAAAAUGUUUUGUUUUUCUUGUGUAUUUAUGAUCACCUAAUUUCACGUUUUGUGAAAUGGACAGUAACCUGUUUCCUGAAAGAUUCCUGUGGGUACUUUUUGAGCUGUGAUAAUAGCAAAAUUGUUUUUCGGUAAUAAUAUCACACUAAUGCUUCUUUUAAACAUUAAACCUAUUUUCCUUUUUUACAGAAUAAGGGAAAAUGUGAUAAGAAGUUUGUAUACAUUUCUGGAUUAUAGAUUAUUAUUUAUCUUUUGAACCAGAGCUAAAUGGUAAAAGAAAAAAAAUCAGUGAUGAUUGUUAUGUUGAUCUCCCACAAUUAAUUUAUCUUUUGACAAAGGGGAUAAAGAGUUUCAGUUUAGCUCCUUUUGAUUGUAUAUUAUUUUUUGCUUUUUUAUUGUGAAAAGAGGUAGGUUUUAUUUGUGGAGAGAGAGUUGAAGAUUAGGGAACCAGUGAUUUUAAUUAUGCUACUUUUUCUUCUAAGAGAUAAAUUGAUAUAUCAUUCAGUGUCAUGAAAAACAUGAAUGUUGUACAAUUUUCUUCCUCAAAAAACUUUUUAAAUGUAAGUAUCCUUAUUUUUUUUUUAAAAGAGCACAAUGUAGGUGUAUUUGAGUAUUUUCAAGAAAAGAAUAAAAACAUUAAUGCAGUAUUAGGUUAACUGGAUAUCAACUAAGCCUUGUUAACAGUUAAAGUAUUAUAACUUUUUUUACUUCUGAAAAUUAAAAAUAAAAUUUAUUUCUGCAAUUUCA